AUGAGAGGCUGUGUGAGAAGCUGCAGCCGCCGGCAGAGGAGACCUCAGCAUCAUCUAGAGCCCAGCGCUGGCCCUGCCUCCGCCUGCCCCGCCGCCGCCGUCGCCGUUUCUGUUCCUGCUACUGUCCCACCUAAACAACUCCCGUUACACGGACAAGUGAACAUCUGUGGCUGUCCUCUCCUUUUCUUCCUCCUCUUCCAACUCCUUCUCCUCCUCCCACUUCCCAGCCGCAGCAGAAAGCCCCCAACCCAACUGACACUGGCACAACUGCAAACGGUGUCAUCCGCACAACUUUAUCUCGCUCCUCGGGCUCCCCUAAGGCAUUGGACCCAUCGCCGCGUCUUUUAUUUUUUGCAAAGUUGCAUCGCUGUACAUAUUUUUGUCCCCGCCACCUCCCUCUGUCUCUGGAGUGCCCUACAGCCCCGCAAACUCCUCCUGGAGCUGCGCCCUAGUGCCCCUGCUGGGCAGUGGCGUUCCCCCCCAUCCUCCCGCGCCCAGCCCCUGCUGCUCUGGGCAGACGAUGCUGAAGAUGCUCUCCUUUAAGCUGCUGCUGCUGGCCGUGGCUCUGGGCUUCUUUGAAGGAGAUGCUAAGUUUGGGGAAAGAAACGAAGGGAGCGGAGCAAGGAGGAGAAGGUGCCUGAAUGGGAACCCCCCGAAGCGCCUGAAAAGGAGAGACAGGAGGAUGAUGUCCCAGCUGGAGCUGCUGAGUGGGGGAGAGAUGCUGUGCGGUGGCUUCUACCCUCGGCUGUCCUGCUGCCUGCGGAGUGACAGCCCGGGGCUAGGGCGCCUGGAGAAUAAGAUAUUUUCUGUUACCAACAACACAGAAUGUGGGAAGUUACUGGAGGAAAUCAAAUGUGCACUUUGCUCUCCACAUUCUCAAAGCCUGUUCCACUCACCUGAGAGAGAAGUCUUGGAAAGAGACCUAGUACUUCCUCUGCUCUGCAAAGACUAUUGCAAAGAAUUCUUUUACACUUGCCGAGGCCAUAUUCCAGGUUUCCUUCAAACAACUGCGGAUGAGUUUUGCUUUUACUAUGCAAGAAAAGAUGGUGGGUUGUGCUUUCCAGAUUUUCCAAGAAAACAAGUCAGAGGACCAGCAUCUAACUACUUGGACCAGAUGGAAGAAUAUGACAAAGUGGAAGAGAUCAGCAGAAAGCACAAACACAACUGCUUCUGUAUUCAGGAGGUUGUGAGUGGGCUGCGGCAGCCCGUUGGUGCCCUGCAUAGUGGGGAUGGCUCGCAACGUCUCUUCAUUCUGGAAAAAGAAGGUUAUGUGAAGAUACUUACCCCUGAAGGAGAAAUUUUCAAGGAGCCUUAUUUGGACAUUCACAAACUUGUUCAAAGUGGAAUAAAGGGAGGAGAUGAAAGAGGACUGCUAAGCCUCGCAUUCCAUCCCAAUUACAAGAAAAAUGGAAAGUUGUAUGUGUCCUAUACCACCAACCAAGAACGGUGGGCUAUCGGGCCUCAUGACCACAUUCUUAGGGUUGUGGAAUACACAGUAUCCAGAAAAAAUCCACACCAAGUUGAUUUGAGAACAGCCAGAGUCUUUCUUGAAGUUGCAGAACUCCACAGAAAGCAUCUGGGAGGACAACUGCUCUUUGGCCCUGACGGCUUUUUGUACAUCAUUCUUGGUGAUGGGAUGAUUACACUGGAUGAUAUGGAAGAAAUGGAUGGGUUAAGUGAUUUCACAGGCUCAGUGCUACGGCUGGAUGUGGACACAGACAUGUGCAACGUGCCUUAUUCCAUACCAAGGAGCAACCCACACUUCAACAGCACCAACCAGCCCCCCGAAGUGUUUGCUCAUGGGCUCCACGAUCCAGGCAGAUGUGCUGUGGAUAGACAUCCCACUGAUAUAAACAUCAAUUUAACGAUACUGUGUUCAGACUCCAAUGGAAAAAACAGAUCAUCAGCCAGAAUUCUACAGAUAAUAAAGGGGAAAGAUUAUGAAAGUGAGCCAUCACUUUUAGAAUUCAAGCCAUUCAGUAAUGGUCCUUUGGUUGGUGGAUUUGUAUACCGGGGCUGCCAGUCAGAAAGAUUGUAUGGAAGCUACGUGUUUGGAGAUCGUAAUGGGAAUUUCCUAACUCUCCAGCAAAGUCCUGUGACAAAGCAGUGGCAAGAAAAACCACUCUGUCUCGGCACUAGUGGGUCCUGUAGAGGCUACUUUUCCGGUCACAUCUUGGGAUUUGGAGAAGAUGAACUAGGUGAAGUUUACAUUUUAUCAAGCAGUAAAAGUAUGACCCAGACUCACAAUGGAAAACUCUACAAAAUUGUAGAUCCCAAAAGACCUUUAAUGCCUGAGGAAUGCAGAGCCACGGUACAACCUGCACAGACACUGACUUCAGAGUGCUCCAGGCUCUGUCGAAACGGCUACUGCACCCCCACGGGAAAGUGCUGCUGCAGUCCAGGCUGGGAGGGGGACUUCUGCAGAACUGCAAAAUGUGAGCCAGCAUGUCGUCAUGGAGGUGUCUGUGUUAGACCGAACAAGUGCCUCUGUAAAAAAGGAUAUCUUGGUCCUCAAUGUGAACAAGUGGACAGAAACAUCCGCAGAGUGACCAGGGCAGGUAUUCUUGAUCAGAUCAUUGACAUGACAUCUUACUUGCUGGAUCUAACAAGUUACAUUGUAUAGUUUCUGGGACUGUUUGAAUAUUCUAUUCCAAUGGGCAUUUAUUUUUUAUCCUGUCAUUAAAAAAAAAAGACUGUUAUCCUGCUACACACUCCUGUGAUUUCAUUCUCUUUUAUUAAUUUAAAAAUAAUUUCCAGAAAUGUGCAGAUCCUCUGUGUGUAUGUCAGCAUGUUUGUUCACAUAUGCACAUACACAUACUCAUAACCCCUAUAUGCGUUGUUGCAUAACAGAUGAUUUUUUAAAAUAUAUACUUCCUUAUGCAAAGUAAUUUACACAGAAAUUCCAUUGUAAAUUGAUAAUGGAUUUUUUAUGUUACUAGAAGAGAUUAUUUGACUUCCCAGGAAUUUUCUGUCUGUAAUCACUAAAGUCAACUUUAAUAGAGUUUUGAAACAGUACUGUGCAAUCCGAUGGAUCUAAUUAAAAAAAAGGCAAUAUUUUUAUAUUAAAGUACUAUACUAGGAGAGAAUGUUUCAGAACUCCCUGAUGAAUUUCUAAGUGAGCAACUUGAUAUAAAAUUGUAAUCUUCAUUUUUGUCAGUGUAUCCAGUUACAGAAUGCUACACACUUACCUUUUUAUUGGCUGAGAAAUCUGGUUAUUUCAUCUUAAUCUCAAGAUUGUUUUCAAGUGUUUUAUAAUUAAAUCAUAAUAGCAUAUUUUAAAAUCAAUCUUCCUAAAAGGUCUGCUUUUAUUGUAUAUUUUAUUUAACAAUAGGCACUGGGUUUGUGUUACAUAUUUAUAUAUUUUAUUUUAUUUUUAUAAUAUAGACAUCACCUAGAUGAAACACCUUUACCCUGUCCUGUAAAACACUAAAGUUACAUUUUUCACCAACUUAAUUGGAAAGAAGGGGAGUGAGAAAGCAAACAGUCUUUAAUGUGCUGUGGAUCUAAUCUAGCAAGGUAUCCUUGUGCCAACAUGUAAUCAUUAACGACGGAUGAAAAAGCAAGAAAACAGCCAAUCCUUAUAAAAUUCCAGCAUUAAACAUUUGUAAAGUGCUUUUCACCAUAGCAAGACUGUCAGAGUCUAUGUUAUUAGAAUGUUGCAGAUUUCCACUGAAUCGAACCUCACUGGAGAAGAGCUCACUUGUUUUUAAAAAUCUUGGCUAUGUAAGCUGUCACCUGUACAAAUUUUUAACAUAAUAAUUCUUGCCAAAUAUGACUUUAAAUGUACGUGUUCCUUCAGAACUCAAUGAAAAUACUCUUUGGCUAAUGUAUCAAUAAAUUUUCUGUAAAUGUUCUGUUCAGGGUUUUACAGAGAUGACAUGUUCUGACUUAAAACUGCAAAAAGUCUAGUAGAUAUUUUUCUUCAUGGUUUUCAAAGCCAGCUCUCCACGUUUGGAUUUUAACAAAAUAUAAGGCCUCUUUGCACUAGUGAAAAAACACGUCUACUCAUGACAAGUGCACACCCACUAUGGCUGUCCUUCUUCUGUAAACAUCCAUUCCUCUAGAAUCUAAAUUGUAGAGCAGUAUAGAUUAUGCAGCGCCAGCUGACUUUCUAAACCUUCUCCUUACCUUUAGGAAUACAAGCCUCAAUUUAAAAAAUAUAUUGUAGCUAGUAUUUCUCUAUUGUUUUAAGGUGAGAGAUUUGCAAUUAAAGCCCAGUAAGCAUUUAUAUAGAAGCCACAAUGUAGAAAGAUUGGUUAAGUACACUGCUCUUGUCUUCCAUAUAUGAUUACUUAAGUUUCAAGUGACCUCAUGCCAAAUGGAAAUGGGUUGAGAAAUCUUGGUUCAGUGCUUAGUGAACAAUAGCCUGCAUUAAAAAGUGCAUGCAUAAUUUUGCACAAUUUAGAUUCAAUUGACAGUCUAUUCAAAGAAGUCUCAGGAUUAAAUGAGCAUGGAGACCAAAUUGCCCUCUUACCCCAGAAAAGGGGUGGUCCCUUCUAGUCACACUAACACUUCAUUGGCCCAACAGUGUGACAAAUCUUGCAAUGAACCAUGCAGUAGCCUGCAUCUGUAGGUUAAUAGCAAUCUUUUGUCUCCAUUGCUUUCUCUUCAUAGCCCUUUUACUGAAUUCCAUCACAGAAAGUUUUACAAUUAAAAAAAAAUGUCCUGACAACCAUUUUUGUAAAUGGACCUUACCAUCUAAUUGUCCCUUAUUCAACGUGGGUGACAUUAACAAAAUGUGAACUUCUUGUGAGGGAGCCAGCUGUCUAAAUCUGUCAAAUCGUGCAGUUUUAUUACACAUUCUCCAAUUCUUCCUAGUUUCCCUGAAAACAAUAAGGAUACUGCUAUAUAUUCAGUAAAAUCUAAAAAAAUCAAGCAUUACUUCUUACAUCUUUAAACUUUCCAUCUCCUCCCCAAAAUAAAAGGUGUUCUAUUGCCAUUAGUUCUACUGUUUUAAAAUAUCUAUAUUAAGUUGACCAGGCCCAGAUUUUUUAUACAGCUUUUUCCCAAGUGAAAGAUUUUCAAGUGACUUAGAAAAACAUAUGUGCCCCAGGUGUCAUUGCCUUUUCUUUUGUGAGUCAUUAGAAUGAAAGGCCAAGUUCUUCUCAAGAGAAGAUAGCAAGAUCCACGGAUAUUAAGCCAAGCAAAGAAAGUAAAAUCAUUGGAGUCAUUUCUUUCUGUUCUUAGGAGAAAAGUAGAUAGCACUGGCUAAUUGAUGGCAACAUAUUUUAAAUUAAGUGGUCAAUUCAAAAAUUCUCUUUGACCUUUUCUUUCAAGUAGAUUUUUUUAAAUGCAUGACUGGAGAAUUAUCUUCAAUGAUUCAUGAUGAGAGGCAGGUAGGAAUUGGUUAAGAAGUAUGAGCAGGAAAAAAUUAUUGUUUAAUCACAUGAAAGGCAACAUCUGUUCAGUUCAUAAAGCACACAGUCUCGAAUGGAAGAAAAAAAGGUCCUUCGUAAGAAUACUGAUGCAUAAGAUAAAGACGAAAUAAUGAAAAAGAAAAAUGUAUAUUAUUAUUCCCUUGUCCAUUCUCAAGUUUAAGCUGCGGUUGUCAGUUGAAUGUGAAAUGAUGUUAUAGUUGUUUUAAAUGGUUGGAAAUAACCUUUCUACUACUGUUUCUGCCACACUGUUGUCCUGGUUCAUAGAACCUUGUUUUCUUGACAGUUAUUUAAGGUAAUAAAAGGAACACAAUUUGGCAGAUCUUUAAGUGAAAGAGAGAAAAAAUUUAAGAAAUUGAGUGAUGGCUAAAAGUAAGUGCUUCCAUCCAUAACUUUUCUUCUUGGAUUUUUUUCAAUGUAAUUAUUGUAAAAUAUAUUUUUUUAUUUUAUCAUGAAGAAUACUCGGAAGGUUUCUCAGAUUAAUGAGUAUCUCAUAAAGAGUAGAGAAACCAACACAUACAAUAUAUACACACAACCUAAAUAGAAAACUAUUUUCUUUGUCAUUUGCAUGCCCCAGAGAAGUUACUUCUUCCCUAUUUAUUUCUUUGAAAAUAAUUACAAAAUAGUAUACUAACAAUUUUAAUCCAUUUGCUGUUUUUUUUUUUUUUUUGGUUUCUUUUUUUUUUUUUUUGAGACGGAGCCUUGCUAUGUUGCCCAGGCUGCAGAGCAGCACAAUCUCAGCUCACUACAACCUCCGCCUCCCGGGUUCAAGCAAUUCUCCUGCCUCAGCCUCCCAAGUAGCUGGGAUUACAGGUGCCCGCCACCACACCCGGCUAAUUUUUUUGUGUUUUUAGUAGAGACAGGGUUUCACCAUGUUGGCCAGGCUGAUUUCAAACUCCAGACUUCAAGUGAUCCAGCCCCCCAGGCCUCCCAAAGUGCUAGGAUUACAGGCGUGAGCCACCAUGCCCAGCUUCCAUUUGCUUUUGAUAUUGUUUUUAUCUCUGAGUUACAAACUAUACAAGCUUACCAGGUAUAAGGUUAGAUGCUACAUCUAGGAGCAUUCAAGAUAUACAUUAAUUUAAACUUUUAUUAGUCUAACUUUCUGUUAAGUCUCUUAGCUUUGAAACAUAAAAGAGAAAUCAAGCCCAAAUUUUUAGAGGAAGGCUAAGGUAUACUAUUGGCAGUUGUAGUUUUAAUUGUAAUUGACUGAUUAACCAAGUAAUUUAUAAAAUGUUACCUAUACUGUCAGUGUUCACCUCCUCUCCCUCCCUCCUUCUCUCUCUCUCUCCCCCUCUCGCUCUCUCGGCUAAUAUAUAUGUGUAUGUGUAUAUAUAUAUGUAUGUAUAUAUAUACACACACACACACACAUACAUACAUACAUACAUAUAUUCUUUUUCCUUUUAACCACUUCCCUCUCCUACAUUUUCUAUUGGUUUUGCCUAAAUAGACAUGUUCUCAAUACACCCAUGUUGAAGGUAUCCUGGGCUAGAUUGCUGUUGAUUUUGCUGGUUAUGAUCUUUUCUUUGUUUUUCUGAAAAAUAGCCUCUCUUGAUUCCACAUUUUCUCAAAUUCUAUAUAACAAAUAAUAGUGGAUAGUAAACAAAUGACAUACUAGGCUGAUCUAUUACAAUCAUUGAAAGAAAUAAGGAAGAGCAGAAAUCACUAACAGUCCAGAGGCUCCAAUUCAGCUGCUCUAGCAUAGAUACAGGAAAGACAUGGAGAAUAACACUGGGGUUAGCUAACAGCAGGGAAAGUUAGUAGCUAUUUCCUAGCCAAGGAACAACCUUCUCUAUGGAAUAAUUUUAAGAAAAUUAUUCCAAAUCUGUGAGGAAAAAAUAAGAAGCAGUUCCUCAAUGGAGACUUUAUAAAUCUUAAUUUCCUCACCCCUGGGAUGAGAUUUGAAGUUGCAGAGGACUCAGACCAAAGUCCCAUGGCAGAAAAUGUACAUAUUUUUAAACUACUCCCAGGAAGUAAACUAGUACUGUGAAUGCUGGCAAUACCAUCAGAAAGUUUAUCUUUAAAAUACCUAAAAAUAAAUAUAUAUUUGCUAUCUUAUCCUCUUUUUGUCACACAAACAUAAAUUGGUCAUAUAUAUAUUUAUAUAUAUGGUUAUAUAUAUUUGGUUAUAUAUAUAUCUUUAUAUAUAUAUCUUAUAUAUAUAUCUUUUUAUAUAUAUCUUAUAUAUAUAUCUUUUUAUAUAUAUCUUAUAUAUAUAUCUUUAUAUAUAUCUUAUAUAUAUAUCUUAUACAUAUAAGAUAUAUGUAUAUAUAUAUACAUUAUAUAUAUAUAAUAUAUAUAUAUUAUAUAUAUAUAAUAUAUAUCUUAUAUAUAUAUAUAUCUUAAUACAUAUAUAUAACCAUGGAACCUGCCAAACACUAAUCCUAGCCAACUUCAAUCCUUCUUUCUCUUAACUAUCUUCUCUGAAUAAGUUCUGGACUUCACCUUAAAAUAAGUUUUUAGGAGAGUAAUAUAUAUUCAUGGGAUUGUGAGGGAGCAUUGUAGAGCUGUUUUCUUCUCAGUCAUAGUGGUGGUUUUCCUAGCUGCUAUGGAAAGGUUUGUUCACUUAUGAGAUUAGGACUUUUCUUAAAUUCCUCAUUAAAUAUGAACCUAAGGCAUACCCAUCAUUUACCUUGAUUCCCAUAUAAUUUGUAUAAGUCAUAUAUAAGUCCAUUGACAAAAUAAAAAAAUAAAUAAUUGGAUUCCUUGUAUCAACAGAAAGCCUUGUGCUUAAAACCUGUUAUUCUUCUUUGAGCCAGACUAAACAGUAACAUUUACAAAAUGGUAUCAGCUCAACAUUAAAUCUAAGGUUACUUCUCACAUACAUCAUAAAGUCAGCCAUCAUCUUUCAUUUAGGAUUUCUUGGGGUUUUCUUUUUGCAUAUAUAGAUUAUGUAUUACUUAAAUCCAAAAUACAUGUGUGUAUAUAUAUACAUAUAUAUGUAACUUAAUAUAAAUGUUUGAUGAGUUAUCUCAAUUGACUAUAAUCUUCUAAGUCAAAAAGAAAACAUUUAAGUACAUAAUAUAAAAAGAACUGAACAUUAACAGUAAUGGGAAAUUCAUAAUGGCUAAAUAUGAAAUAAGCUUUGUCUUUGCAGUUACAAACUAAUUCUUGUACAUUUUCCUUUUCACUAAAAAAAUAACUAAUUGAUAGUUUCCAUUCACAUGAACAAGUUAUAAUCAGGUUUGGGAUAGUAUGCCCAAAACCUAUGUUUCUUUACUUUAUAUUCUUAAAAUCUGAGACAUGAUUUUUCUGGAACAAAUUAAGAUUUCAUGUACAAUAGAGUCCCUUUCCUAAUACUGUUAUGAAGAAACCAAGUUGACUACCUUAUGAGAGAUCAGAUAUUUCCCUUAUCUCAUUAUAUUCACAGCAUAUGUUUGGACAUGCGUUUCACCAAGAACCAUGUAGUAAUAAGAUAAAUGGUAACUGAGGUACUAUGGAAUUUUUAGAACUUGAUUCCCCAGGACAUGCUACAGUAAACUAAACUAUUUAUUCAAAAGUAACCCAACUAAUUAAAGUGAAAAAAAAUUGUUGAAUCACAAUGAACAAACAUAAAACAAUACUUAAAUGAGAAUUCUGUGUCUUUUUUGGUUUUAUCUGUGAUUUAUUUUGUCCAGUAUUAAGGAAUGGUUAUCUUUAUCAUUCUUCUAACAUGUUUUGGUUUCUCUAAUGGUUCAUUUUCCUUUAGCUUGUGAAAAUUAGGGCAGUUUGUCCAGAGCCUUACUCGCAGGAGACACCAGACCCAACCCAUGCUUAGAUUUCUGUUAAUAAAAGGGAGAAGGGUAUUUGAAUAGGUAGUAAAGGCAGGUACAAGUUUAAGGGAGCAGGGCUAUCAUAUGUACUAGGUGAGAUUUCUAUAAAUGUCUGAAAAGUUACAUGCAUAGUCAUUGGCUCAGGUAAUUUCUCUGAAUUUGAACUUAUUUGAUUUAUUUAACCAAGUUAUUAUAAUAUGCAGUUCUCUUUAAUCAAUCUUCUAUUAUUCAAUCAUCUAUCCAUUUAUUAAUUCAACAAAUAUUUAUUAAAGUGCCUACCAUGAUUAUGUGCUGUAGAAAAGACAAGGACAUUUACUAGGGGGGGAUUGUGGGCCCAAUCGGCAUCAUAAGCAUGUCUGAAGCAAAAGACAAUAAUCACAUCCAACGGCACCAGUUCAGCUCAACUUUAGAAUUCAGCAGUAACAGUACAGAUGGCCUAAAGUACAUCUGUGUGUAUCUGUACGUGUGCACACACCCAUGUAUAUAUAUUUAUCUAUCUGUACAAACACUACAUAUGUAUACACACUAUCUAUGUAAAAUAUAAUAUAUGUAUAAUGCAUAUAAAUUCUAACAAGUGUAUUUGUGUUAUCUUUAAAAUAGAACAAUUGUAUCUUGAAGUGGUAAAUGCAGAGAAUUGGUUUUAUUGUUGAUCUGUGGAUUUAAUGAUUUCUAGGUGAAAAGGACGUUUAAGUGUACAAUUUCUUUUCUUAAUUUAAUAUAUUUAUGUAAAUGCAUGCCUGAAAUUUGGUUAGAUUGGCUGUGUUUUGUGUCUUUUAACAUGAUCAAAUGAUUAAACUUUAUCUUAUGACUUGA